ACACUCAUGCUGCAGCCUUGAGCCGUCCCUCGUCCUCCUCUCAGGCUCCCUCUUGUCCACGGCGGGCGGGCGCCGAGCUGCUGAUGUGUCCCUAGCAUAACCUGGCCCCAUUCCUUUGCAUCUAGAUGCCUUUGGACAAGGCUAUGCCACUGAAGCAUUAUCUCCUUUUGCUGGUGGGCUGCCAAGCCUGGGGUGCAGGGUUGGCCUACCAUGGCUGCCCUAGCGAGUGUACCUGCUCCAGGGCCUCCCAGGUGGAGUGCACCGGGGCACGCAUUGUGGCAGUGCCCACCCCUCUGCCCUGGAACGCCAUGAGCCUGCAGAUCCUCAACACGCACAUCACUGAACUCAAUGAGUCCCCGUUCCUCAAUAUCUCAGCCCUCAUCGCCCUGAGGAUUGAGAAGAAUGAGCUGUCGCGCAUCACGCCUGGGGCCUUCCGAAACCUGGGCUCGCUGCGCUAUCUCAGCCUCGCCAACAACAAGCUGCAGGUUCUGCCCAUCGGCCUCUUCCAGGGCCUGGACAGCCUCGAGUCUCUCCUUCUGUCCAGUAACCAGCUGUUGCAGAUCCAGCCGGCCCACUUCUCCCAGUGCAGCAACCUCAAGGAGCUGCAGUUGCACGGCAACCACCUGGAAUACAUCCCUGACGGAGCCUUCGACCACCUGGUAGGACUCACGAAGCUCAAUCUGGGCAAGAAUAGCCUCACCCACAUCUCACCCAGGGUCUUCCAGCACCUGGGCAACCUCCAGGUCCUCCGGCUGUAUGAGAACAGGCUCACGGAUAUCCCCAUGGGCACUUUUGAUGGGCUUGUUAACCUGCAGGAACUGGCUCUGCAGCAGAACCAGAUUGGACUGCUCUCCCCUGGUCUCUUCCACAACAACCACAACCUCCAGAGACUCUACCUGUCCAACAACCACAUCUCCCAGCUGCCACCCAGCGUCUUCAUGCAGCUGCCCCAGCUCAACCGUCUUACUCUCUUUGGGAAUUCCCUGAAGGAGCUCUCUCCGGGGAUCUUCGGGCCCAUGCCCAACCUGCGGGAGCUUUGGCUCUAUGACAACCACAUCUCUUCUCUACCCGACAAUGUCUUCAGCAACCUCCGCCAGUUGCAGGUCCUGAUUCUUAGCCGCAAUCAGAUCAGCUUCAUCUCCCCGGGUGCCUUCAACGGGCUAACGGAGCUUCGGGAGCUGUCCCUCCACACCAACGCACUGCAGGACCUGGACGGGAACGUCUUCCGCAUGUUGGCCAACCUGCAGAACAUCUCCCUGCAGAACAACCGCCUCAGACAGCUCCCAGGGAAUAUCUUCGCCAACGUCAAUGGCCUCAUGGCCAUCCAGCUGCAGAACAACCAGCUGGAGAACUUGCCCCUCGGCAUCUUCGAUCACCUGGGGAAACUGUGUGAGCUGCGGCUGUAUGACAAUCCCUGGAGGUGUGACUCAGACAUCCUUCCGCUCCGCAACUGGCUCCUGCUCAACCAGCCUAGGUUAGGGACGGACACUGUACCUGUGUGUUUCAGCCCAGCCAAUGUCCGAGGCCAGUCCCUCAUUAUCAUCAAUGUCAACGUUGCUGUUCCAAGCGUCCAUGUCCCCGAGGUGCCUAGUUACCCAGAAACACCAUGGUACCCAGACACACCCAGUUACCCUGACACCACAUCCGUCUCUUCUACCACUGAGCUAACCAGCCCUGUGGAAGACUACACUGAUCUGACUACCAUUCAGGUCACUGAUGACCGCAGCGUUUGGGGCAUGACCCAGGCCCAGAGCGGGCUGGCCAUUGCCGCCAUUGUAAUUGGCAUUGUCGCCCUGGCCUGCUCCCUGGCUGCCUGCGUCGGCUGUUGCUGCUGCAAGAAGAGGAGCCAAGCUGUCCUGAUGCAGAUGAAGGCACCCAAUGAGUGUUAAAGAGGCAGGCUGGAGCAGGGCUGGGGAAUGAUGGGACUGGAGGACCUGGGAAUUUCAUCUUUCUGCCUCCACCCCUGGGUCCAUGGAGCUUUCCCGUGAUUGCUCUUUCUGGCCCCAGAGAAAGGUGAGCCUACCUCUUCCUGACUUGCCUGAUUCUCCCGUAGAGAAGCAGGUCGUGCCGGACCUUCCUACAAUCAGGAAGAUAGAUCCAACUGGCCAUGGCAAAAGCCCUGGGGAUUUCCGAUUCAUACCCCUGGGCUUCCUUCGAGAGGGCUCUUCCUCCAAAUCCUCCCCACCUGUCCUCCAAGAACAGCCUUCCCUGCGCCCAGGCCCCCUCCGGGCCUCUGUAGACUCAGUUAGUCCACAGCCUGCUCACUUCGUGGGAAUAGUUCUCCGCUGAGAUAGCCCCUCUCGCCUAAGUAUUAUGUAAGUUGAUUUCCCUUCUUUUGUUUCUCUUGUUUGUGCUACGGCUUGACCCAGCAUGUCCCCUCAAAUGAAAGUUCUCCCCUUGAUUUUCUGCUCCUGAAGGCAGGGUGAGUUCUCUCCUCAAAGAAGACUUCAAACCAUUUAACUGGUUUCUUAAGAGCCGUCAAUCAGCCUGGUUUUGGGGAUGCUAUGAAAGAGAGAAGGAAAAUCAUGCCGCUCAGUUCCUGGAGACAGAAGAGCCGUCAUCAGUGUCUCACUUGUGAUUUUUAUCUGGAAAAGGAAGAAACACCCCAGCACAGCAAGCUCAGCCUUUUAGAGAAGGAUAUUUCCAAACUGCAAACUUUGCUUUGAAAAGUUUAGCCCUUUAAGGAAUGAAAUCAUGUAGAAUUUUGGACUUCUAAAAACAUUAAAAUCAGCUUAUUAAUACGGGAUAGAGAAAGAAAUCUGGUGCCUGGGGGUCCCUGUGUUCACCCCUAGAGUUUGUUUUAAAAUUUUUAAUUGAAGCAUGUGAAGUGUACGUGCAGAAAAGUGGGAACAUGAUAGUGUAUGGCUUGGUGGAUUUUCACAAACUGAACAUACCUGUGUAAUCAGCAUCUAGACCCAGACCCAGAGCAUCACAAAUAUCCCCCAUCCUGGGCUUUUCCCAGAGGAGAUGGGGGCUUCUGAAGAUGGACUUACCUGGGACCUGCCCCCCAUGAGCCAGGACGGUCCCCCCACAGUCAGCCUGUGCAAAGGCCCCGUGGCCAGGGGUGGAGGAGAAUAUGUGGGUGUGGACAGGAUGGGAGACUGUGGCCUGAACAGGAGAUUUUAUUAUAUCUGGAGACCCUGAGAGACCCUGAGACCUGGGGCACCAUGGCUGGCCAGGUCAGAAGCAUCCUGACUGCAGAGGUCCGUGCAGCCACACCCUCUUCCCUGCCAGCAAGCUGUCUGCGGCUCAUCGGAGGCCCCUCCGCCUGGAGCCUUCUAUGGACGUGAUAUGCCUGUAUCUGUUUUUAAUUUUCAUUCUUCACUUAGGGGAAGUGAAAUCGCUCAGAGAUGAGAUCCUUUAAUUGAAAACGAAGUGUAACGGAAUCUAGUGUCUUUCUAAUGUGGUAAAAUUCUCCAUCAACAUCACAGUCAGCUGGCAGCUGAACUUCAGAAUCUCACUUACAGCAGGCGACACGGGGGUACACCGAUGGGUCACACUGGGUCUGGGGGCUCCCUGGAGCUCCUCCUGCGUGUGGUCUGGUUAGGAGUUGAGUUGUUUGCUCCAGGGUUAUUCUCCUCCUCGAGUCACAGUCACACGAAUACCUGCCUUCUCUGGCUUUCCUGCUAUACACAUAUUCACAUGGCGCUCAAGAAGUUAGGCUCAUGGCAACGUGUGUCUUUCUCUGGACAACUGGCCCAGUUUACAGUGAAAUGGAGAAUUUCAGGUCUCCACGUCUGCCCAGGAAAGAACUUCAGCUGACUCCACGGGGAUCUGGAAAUCCACGACCAAUCCCGAUCGGCUCUUAUUAGCUCCCCGCUCCACAAGACACCUGUGCUUUGGAAAUCCACCACCAAUCCCGAUCGGCUCUUAUUAGCUCCCCGCUCCACAAGACACCUGUGAUCUGGAAAUCUACCACCAAUCCCGAUCGGCUCUUAUUAGCUCCCCGCUCCACAAGACACCUGUGACAUCCUCCAGGGCCACAGGAGCACGUGCUGACCAGUUUUCCCUUCCAGUUCCUGCACAAAAAGUGUCCAGAGGGCUGUUUGCAAACACUAGUGCACUUUGUAGCUUUUCACCCUCUGUCCCAGGGAAUCUAGGAGAGAUGAGGCCCGUCAGAGUCAAGAGAUGUCAUCCCCCCAGGGUCUCCAAGGCAUUUCCACACUAUUGGUGGCACCUGGAGGACAUGCACCAAGGCUUGCCAGAGCCAACAGGAAGUGAGCCCAGAGCAUGGCACAUGAGCAUCACCCGCUGAUGGUGGCCUGCUGUGCCUGGUGCCAACAGGGGCAUCCCGGCCCGUACCCCUCCAGACAGGAAGCAUGGGUUUGCCCACAGACCUGUCGGGUGCUCCUGUGAGUGGCCUCCAGAUGUCUUUGUGCAUAGGCACAAGUGGGCCAGGGCUGGAGGGAGGUGGGAAACCUCAUCAUCCGGUGGGCCCUGCCAAUCUUAACCCAGAACCCUUAGGUAUUCCUGGCAGUAGCCAUGACAUUGGAGCACCUUCCUCUCCAGCCAGAGGCUGACCUGAGGGCCACUGUCCUCAGAUGACACCACCCAGGAGCACCCUAGGUGAGGGGUGAGGGCCCCCUUAUGUGAACCUCUUGCCUCUUCCUUUCUCCCAUCAGAGUGGUUGGAUGGAGCCAUUGGCCUCCUUUUCUUCAGCGGGCCCUUCAACCUCUCUGCACCAUGUUGUCUGGCUGAGGAGCUACUAGAAAAGCUGAGUGGAGUCUCCUUUCCAACAGGAUGAUGCAUUUGCUCAAUUCUCAGGGCUGGAAUGAGCCGGCUGGUCCCCCAGAAAGCUGGAGUGGGGUACAGAGUUCAGUUUUCCUCUCUGUUUACAGCUCCUUGACAGUCCCACGCCCAUCUGGAGUGGGAGCUGGGAGUCAGUGUUGGAGAAGAAACAACAAAAGCCAAUUAGAACCACUAUUUUUAAAAAGUGCUUACUGUGCACAGAUACUCUUCAAGCACUGGACGUGGAUUCUCUCUCUAGCCCUCAGCACCCCUGCGGUAGGAGUGCCGCCUCUACCCACUUGUGAUGGGGUACAGAGGCACUUGCUCUUCUGCAUGGUGUUCAAUAGGCUGGGAGUUUUAUUUAUCUCUUCAAACUUUGUACAAGAGCUCAUGGCUUGUCUUGGGCUUUCGUCAUUAAACCAAAGGAAAUGGAAGCCAUUCCCCUGUUGCUCUCCUUAGUCUUGGUCAUCAGAACCUCACUUGGUACCAUAUAGAUCAAAAGCUUUGUAACCACAGGAAAAAAUAAACUCUUCCAUCCCUUAAAGAAUAGAAUAGUUUGUCCCUCUCAUGGGAAUUGGGCUGUAUGUAUAUUGUUCUUCCUCCUUAGAAUUUAGAGAUACAAGAGUUCUACUUAGAACUUUUCAUGGACACAAUUUCCACAACCUUUCAGAUGCUGAUGUAGAGCUAUUGGGAAAGAACUUCCAAACUCAGGAAGUUUGCAGAGAGCAGACAGCUAGAGAUAACUCGGGACCCAGAGUUGGUCGACAGAUGUUAGAUGUAUCCUAGCUUUUAGCUAUAAACCACUCAAAGAUUCAGCCCCCAGAUCCCACAGUCAGAACUGAAUCUGCGUUGUUGGGAAGCCAGCAGUGGCCUUGGGAAGGAAGCCAUGGCUGUGGUUCAGAGAGGGUGGGCUGGCAAGCCACUUCCGGGGAAAACUCCUUCCGCCCCAGGUUUCUUCUUCUCUUAAGGAGAGAUUGUUCUCACCAACCCGCUGCCUUCAUGCUGCCUUCAAAGCUAGAUCAUGUUUGCCUUGCUUAGAGAAUUACUGCAAAUCAGCCCCAGUGCUUGGCGAUGCAUUUACAGAUUUCUAGGCCCUCAGGGUUUUGUAGAGUGUGAGCCCUGGUGGGCAGGGUUGGGGGGUCUGUCUUCUGCUGGAUGCUGCUUGUAAUCCAUUUGGUGUACAGAAUCAACAAUAAAUAAUAUACAUGUA